AACAAAAAAAAAAAAAAAAAAGAAAGAAAAAGAAAUUCAGUGACUUCUGAAAGUCAAGAAAUCUUUGUGACUCUCACAAGAACCAUAAGCGGUAUUUUAACGCAGCUUCCCAUAUUUACAGGAAGAUUAUGUCUUCUUUUUCCAAAGAGCUGAGACAGAAAUAUAAUGUUCGGUCCAUGCCCAUCUGAAAGGAUGAAGAAGCUCAGUUUGCACAAGGACACUAUAGAGGUCAGCAAAUUAGCAAAGUAGUCCAAGUUUAUGGGAAGAAAUACGUUGUCUGCACUGGACAUAUGCAGCGGGAGAAGGCUGGCCAUUUGCCCCAGCAGGGCUCUUAACCCUGAACAAAGACUGAGAUCCUUGAGCCAAAAGCUAAAUCUCACCAAGUAGGAACAGAAAAGGCCAAAUACAAGGAAAAUGCAAUUGGGAAGAUGUAGGAAUAAAGUAAUCUUACAUACAUCUUUCAUUAAAAAACUGCUGCAAUGAACAGGAAAAAAAGUCAUAAGAGAGAAUCAAGCCAAAACAUUAGCUAUGAAAAAUUUAAGAUUUAAAAAAUAAAAGACAUAAUAGAUGGCCUGAAUAUCAGGAUGGAUACAACUGAAGAAUUUGCGAGUAGAUAGGAUGAUCAGAUUGAGAAUUAUCCCCAAAAGCAACAGGGAAAGAAACAGAGACAACACAUAGAAAAGAGAAGCUGAGAGAGGCCAGGCGCAGUGGCUCACGCCUGUAAUCCCAGCACUUGGGGAGGCUGAGGCAGGCAGAUCAUUUGAGAUCAGGAGUUUGAUACCAGCCUGGCCAAUAUGGUGAAACCCCAUCACUACUAAAAAUACAAAAAUUAGCUCGGUGUGGUGGUGGGCGCCUGUAAUUCCAGCUACUCGGGAGGCUGAGGCAAGAGAAGAAUCACUUGAACCCGGGAGACUGGAGGUUGCAGUGACCUGAAAUCACGCCACUGCACUCCAGCCUGGGCAACAGAGUGAGAUUCUGUCUCAAAAAAAAAAAAAAAAAAACAAAAAAAAACCUGAGAGAGAUGGAGAGUAUACGUAUGAUUCCCAAAAGGAAAGAAAAAUAAAAGUGGAGAUGAGGAAAUAAAUAAUUGACGAAAUAAUGGAGAUUUAAAUGUUCCAAAAAUGUUUUUUAAAUGAGUACAGAUUGAAAGAGCUCAUAGAGUAACCAACAGUAGAAAAGAAUAAGGAAAAAUUCACACAUAGGUAUCAGGGGGAAAUUAAGAAUAUGAAAGACCAGGAAGAAGAGCAGGGAGAAAUAACAGAUGGCGUACAGAGGAACAAGAACUGGGUUGGCAUUAUUCUUCUCAACAGCAAUACCCGAUAAAGUCAAAGAAGUGAUGUCACUAGUAAUUUAAAAAAAAGAACUCUUUCAAUCCAGAAUUUUAAAGCCAGCCAAUUUGUCAUUCAAACAUGAGGUCAUAAUAAAAAUAUUCUUAGGCAAAUAAAGCCUCAGAAGGUGGAAUACACAAAGACCCACAUUGAAAAUACUCUUGCAGGAAAUAAAUAAUGAAAGAAAUGUUCAGGAGAUCCUGCAAGAACUGUGGGAAGUCAGGCUUCAGUGCAAGAAAUAGAAGCAGUAUUUGGCAUUUUAGGCAGGAGGGGAUUUUAUACACCUUUUUUUUUUUUUUUAAUGUAGGAAAGGCUAGAGGCUCCCAAAAUACUGCAAAACUGGCCAGACUGGGGAGCUACAGCAUCUGCCAUAACCAGGAAAGUGGAGGAAUCUCAAGGCUGCCCUGGAGGUUGAAACUGAACUUGACAGGGAACUGUUGAAUUCAAGGACACAUACAUCCUGGAUCCAGGGACCUGGAAGCUGAUACACUGUAACUGCCCAGAUAUUGGAACCCAGAGUCUGGGUACCAAUGUCACUGCAACACUUGUUCUCUUUUCAACAAGGAGAGAGAUCGAGAUGACCACAGCCACCCCUCUGGGGGAUACCACCUUCUUCUCACUGAACAUGACCACCAGGGGAGAAGACUUCCUGUAUAAGAGUUCUGGAGCCAUUGUUGCUGCCGUUGUGGUGGUUGUCAUCAUCAUCUUCACCGUGGUUCUGAUCCUGCUGAAGAUGUACAACAGGAAAAUGAGGACGAGGCGGGAACUAGAGCCCAAGGGCCCCAAGCCAACCGCCCCUUCUGCCGUGGGCCCAAACAGCAACGGCAGCCAACACCCAGCAACUGUGACCUUCAGUCCUGUUGACGUCCAGGUGGAGACGCGAUGACCUCUACCCUGGCGCUAUCUCCACCACUGUCCAAAGAGCCUCUCCAGAGUCAAGACCCAGAGGCACACUCUCUGGCAGCUUCACAAUGAGCUUCUUCUGGUCAGGUCGACAGAGACAUCUUUGACGCAAUCUCUGAUGCUUCCAGCAAUCCUCAACCUUGUCUGCCCUGCCCUACCCCAACUGUGUCCACAUCCCUGCCGCCACCCCACCAAAAAGCUGCAGAACAUUCUUUUGUCAUCUGAUGAGGUAGAGCUAUGUUGGGAAUCCACCAAUGUGGGCUUGGCUUUCCCCCACACUGUAGUUAGACAGAUAGACAGAUAGCCCAGGAGCCAGGUGUCAGGGAGCACUGCUGAGAGUAUCACAAUAGGAUCUGUCACGGGGUUCAUAUCAGAUGAAGCGCCGUAUCCACUGCUUCACAGAGCAAAACAUUCAAUCCCAUAACCAGGCACAGGGGAACUAACUUGGACUAACUAACCAGAAAACCUUGUUAACGUAUAACUUGUUCCAGUACUACAUCUCUGCCUGCUGGCUCAUGACAAUUGCUCAGCACAUUUUCCCCUCUUGAAGAAAGGUUGCAAGAAGAACUAAAUUAUCCUCAAAAGAUUUCUGCUUCAUUAGUAAAGAGUCAGUGAUGGAAUAGGGUGACUCUGCAGAAUAGUGGCCUCUAGGGUAGGAGCUUGUUGUGUUGUCCGUGGGCCUGGAAUGAUCCUGGUGGCUGAUCAGGGUCCUUCUCCCACUCUGGGCUGUAUCAACCCUGACGGUCUUGGUCUUUGGCUCCCCUUUAUCUGGAUUCUGAGCACGCUGACUGUCCUGUUAAUGCCUUCCCUCCAAGGACCAGUAUUUGGAGAUUAAUUAGAUUACAACUCUAUCUAUGUUACCUUUGUCCUUCCUGGUCACCUUGCAGAUUCAAGACAUGUUCAAAGCAACACAUUCACAACCCAUUUCUAUUCUAUAGCAACCUCGUCUGUGACUCCUUAGCCUGGAGAACAAUCUACCAAGAAGAGAAAGUAUCUGGAAUUAAGAAGUCCUACCAUCCAAGCCCUACUUCCUGGUUGUGUGGCCUUGGAAAAGUGACUCAACCUCUUUAUAUUCAGUUUCCUAACCAUGAAGUGGAAAUGAUAACACCUGCCUCAUUGGGGCACUAUAACAAGUGAAGGACUUAGGAAAACAUCUGGAGUAUAGCGCCUGGCACCCAGGAGAUGCUUAAUAAAUGGGAACCAGGAUUCUUUUUCUUUUCUUUUUUCUUUUCUUUUUUUUUUUUUUUUGAGACAGAGCCUCAAUCUGUCACCUGGGCUGGAGUGCAGUGGCACGCUCACAGCUCGCUGCAGCCUUGAACUCCUGGGCUCAAGGGAUGCUCCCUCCUCAGCCUCCAGAGUAGCUGGGACUACAGGUAUGUGUCACCUCACCAGGCUAAUUUUUUUAUUUUUUAUUUUUGUAGAGAUGGGGUCUCGCUGUGUUGCCCAGGCUGGUCUUGAACCCCUGGCCUCAAGUGAUCCUUCUGCUUUGGCCUCCCAAAGUGCUGGGAUUACAGGCAUGGACUAUGGUGCCCAGCCUAGGAGCCAACAUUAUUAUUAUUAUAGGCUUUUUUUUCAAUUGCAAGAUAGACAUUUCUUCACAUUUUAAUGAUUCUGAAAUCAGAACAUAUCUUGCAAUUGAUGGGUUCAUUAAUAUAAUUGUAGUUCUUUACUUCCUCUCAAAAACUUGUGAUCUUAUAAUUGAUGGCAUCUUGGAAACAAGGUAAUAAAUCUCUAUUCUGUUAAAGAAAGUGACACACUUUGACAUUUAACCUCAAAUUUUAGGAGUCUCUCCCUCUUGGGGUCAGAAAUCCCUUCUGAGGCCAGGUGUCGUGGCUCAUGCCUGUAAUCCCAGCACUUUGGGAGGCUGAGGCAGGCGGGUCACUUGAGGUCAGGAGUUUGAGACCAGCCUGGCCAACAUGGCAAAACCCUGUCUCUACUAAUAAUACAAAAUUUAGCUGGGCAUGGUGGCAUGCACCUGUAAUCCCACUACUAGGGAGGCUGUGGCAUGAGAAUCACUUGAACCUGGAAGGCAGAGGUUGCAGUGAGCCAAGAUCGUGCCACUGCACUCCAGCCUGGGCAACAGAGUGAAACUGCAUCUCAAAAAAAGAAAAAUCCAUUAUGAGGGGAAAUCAAGAGUCAGGGAGGUAAGAGGUCUUACCCAGGGUCACACAGCUCAUGAUAUCCCACUGUAAAAAUACUCUGUGGAAUAGCUCUGGAGAAAUACUGGCACAUUCUUCCUCUCUGGUCAUUAUUUCUUCCUACUGUGUUUAAAUAUCCACCAAGUGUCAAGGACUUUGUAAGAUGCUUUCACAUAAAUUAUCUCAUAGGAUUAAAUUUUCCCAAAAACCUGGGGAGGAAUUAUUUUUUCCAAAACAGAUGAUAAUUUCUGAUUCAAAGAGAAAGAAAACAAAGUACUUUUCCAAAGUCACACAGCUAGUAAGUCACAAAGACAAGACUCAAAACCAGGUCUCUUGACUCCAAAGUCUGUCUUUUUUGUGAAGUCACACUCCUCUGCUGGCCCAGCUCAAAGCAGCACAGAUUCUUUAUGGGCUGAACAAGGGGAGUACGGGUUUGUCCAUGUGUUUGAGUAGAGAUCAGGGUUCUGGCUUCCAGGCUGAAGGUGAGGGAAAAGCCACUUCUAACUCCUUUGGGCAUCCAUGCUCACGGCCAAAAGAGCCCCUUCUCAACACAUCCAAGUGCUAAGGAUUCCUGCUUCAUUCAAGCUACUACUUAGGCCCAAGGAGCAAGGGGUAGAAUGGCAUCUAACCAGAGCAAAGCCAUUUCUUUGAGGGCUCAAGCCAUAAACAAAUAUGCUCCCCUAAACAUAUUCGGCUUGAAAAAGUUGUUUUGGGGCAGCUGUGGUGGUGCACCCCUGUAAUCCCAGCCCUUUGGGAGUCAGAGGCAGUCAGUCACUUGAGCCCAGGAGUUCAAGACUAGCCUGGGCAACACGGCGAAACCUCGUCUCUACAAAAAAUACAAAAAUUAACCAAGCGUGGUAGUGCACGCCUGUAUUCCCAGCUACUUGGGAGGCUGAGGUAGGAGGAUGGCUUGAGCCUGGGAGGCAGAGGUUGCAGUGAGCUGAGAUCGCGCCACUGCACUCCAGCCGGGGUGACAGAGCCAGACCCUGUCUCAAAGCAUAUUUCAACCCUAAAACUAGACUCUUCUGCCCACAGUGCAGUCUUCUAAGGGUUACCCUCUGGUAUAUGUUCUUUUGCUAAAUGAAGGCUUGGAGUUGGAGGGAAGAAGGGGAGAUGGAGUGGUGAGGGCGAGUCAAAUAAAAGGAUUUGAGUGUCUCGUUUUUGACUAAUGAAGAUGAUUCAAUAAACAUCCUGUAAGAAGGGUUCCUAUGUGCAAGUUGAGGUGCUACUAAGUACAUUAAGACACAAUUGCUGCUCUCAAGGAGUUAGCAGCUGGUCUCAUGCAGGGAUCUCACCACGUGGUUAUGUAUUUUGUUUCUGAUGAGGUGCCUUUCUUAGCAGAUGCUGCCUUAUUUGGCCACUGAAACAAUCAAAGCUAAUAAAUGCUUAAAGAAAAAUAUCUGACAAUAAAAAGGUUUAAAUCAAA